GGAAGUGGAGGUGAGCUGUCGCGGGCGGCGCCCGGCCUUGCUCAACGCCCAGCAGUCCCCACCGUCGCUGCCGCCGCCACCGCCCUCGGCCGCUGCCGAGGCCUCCUGCAGCCAUCAUGUCCGCCAGCGCCGUCUACGUGCUGGACCUGAAGGGCAAGGUGCUCAUCUGCCGGAACUACCGUGGCGACGUGGACAUGUCAGAGGUGGAGCACUUCAUGCCCAUCCUGAUGGAGAAGGAGGAGGAGGGGAUGCUGUCGCCCAUCCUGGCCCACGGGGGGGUCCGUUUCAUGUGGAUCAAACACAACAACCUGUAUCUGGUUGCCACAUCCAAGAAGAACGCGUGCGUGUCGCUGGUCUUUUCUUUCCUCUAUAAGGUGGUGCAGGUGUUUUCCGAGUACUUCAAGGAGCUGGAGGAGGAGAGCAUCCGGGACAACUUUGUUAUCAUCUACGAGCUGCUGGACGAGCUCAUGGACUUCGGCUACCCCCAGACCACCGACAGCAAGAUCCUGCAGGAGUACAUCACUCAGGAAGGCCACAAGCUGGAAACAGGGGCCCCGCGGCCACCAGCCACCGUCACCAACGCGGUGUCCUGGCGGUCCGAAGGCAUCAAGUAUCGGAAGAAUGAGGUGUUCUUGGACGUCAUCGAGUCUGUCAACCUCUUGGGUAAAUACCCAGGAGUGGGAUGGCUGGGUCACACGGUCAGCGCCAACGGCAAUGUCCUGCGCAGCGAGAUCGUGGGCUCCAUCAAGAUGCGAGUCUUCCUCUCGGGCAUGCCCGAGCUGCGCCUGGGCCUCAACGACAAGGUCCUCUUUGACAACACGGGCCGCGGCAAAAGCAAAUCCGUGGAGCUGGAGGAUGUGAAGUUCCACCAGUGUGUGCGGCUAUCACGCUUCGAGAAUGACCGCACCAUCUCCUUCAUCCCACCCGACGGCGAGUUCGAGCUCAUGUCCUACCGUCUCAACACCCACGUCAAGCCUUUGAUAUGGAUCGAGUCGGUGAUCGAGAAGCACUCCCACAGCCGCAUCGAGUACAUGAUCAAGGCCAAAAGCCAGUUCAAGCGGCGGUCAACAGCCAACAACGUGGAGAUCCACAUUCCCGUGCCCAAUGAUGCCGACUCACCCAAGUUCAAGACGACGGUGGGGAGCGUUAAGUGGGUCCCCGAGAACAGCGAGAUCGUGUGGUCCAUCAAGUCCUUCCCGGGCGGCAAGGAGUACCUGAUGCGGGCCCACUUCGGCCUGCCUAGUGUGGAGGCCGAAGACAAGGAGGGCAAGCCCCCGAUCAGUGUCAAGUUCGAGAUCCCUUACUUCACUACCUCCGGCAUCCAGGUGCGCUACCUGAAGAUCAUUGAGAAGAGUGGGUACCAGGCCCUGCCCUGGGUGCGUUAUAUCACGCAGAAUGGAGAUUACCAGCUCCGGACCCAGUGAGGGGCUGUCGCAGCCAACACCCCGGCCUCGGGGCUCCUGGUGGCAGCACCAGGGGACACACCUGCCAAACCCACCAGAUGGAGGGGCCCUCCCUGGUCUCUGGCCACCCUCCCAGCCUCUGCCCAGGGACCCCUGCCUUCCCCAGGCCAUCUGCUCUGCCGUCGACACUCGUCUCAGAAGCCCCUUUCCCAGAAGAGGCUGGUCUUCAAGAAGUCUCGUUUCUUUGCCCCUGAAGUCAGUUUCAGGGGAAGGAUGUGAAAUUUUUCCGUGUAGAGGUUACAGCCUUUUAUGCUGUUGAGCUCCCAGGUACCAAAAAGCUUGGCCAACGCUUGCCAGCCAGCCAGCUGCAGGUGGCAUCUGCCACGAAGGAAGCGCCAGCCUCGCCAGGCCAGCAGGGGCGUCGUUUUGUUGCCAUUUUGUUGAACGUUAUGGGUUUAUGGGUGUUCCUGGAACUUGUCUUUGUGCAUUCGUUGCUGUUUGUGUUACCCUCACUGUCCCCAUGUCCCACCCACGUCCUACGGCACUCAGGAAGCACUUGGUGAGGACGAGCCCUCACCCUUCUUGUCUUCCUUCCCGGCAGCGCCCGCAGCGGGCCAUUUACACGUCGAGGCUGGCACCUGGCGCGCUCGGGGGCCACUGUAGCGUCUGCCUGCUCCCUGGACUCGCAGGCCUCGCCUGUGGCGCCUUCCCAGGGCCAGCCUGGGUCACGAGAUGCUGUCACUCAGCCAGAUCAGUAUUGACCCACCAGGGGAGGUGGGGUUUGGUGAGAGACGCCAGCCUCAGACUUUUUCCCACUGAGGGUCCAGAGAGCGGGGCCACGUGUCACCCACGUCUGCGCUUGGUCACCCGUCCUCCCCACCCUGUGUGUGUUUAUGUCAUAGUUACAUUAAAUUCCAUUCAUUGAAUACUCCACAGCCUUCCUCUGAUGCAGCGUGGUCCCAACUCCUCCUGCGUGACCACAGGGCUUGCCUGGUUUUGUCGCCGACCUUCCCUGUGGCCCCACGAGGUGUCACCAGCUCCCUCUGCUUCCCCAGCUGAAACACAGGAAAAGCAGCUGCGGGAAGAGGCAGCUGCAGUGCUGGACCAUGGGCCACCACUCCUGGGCCACACAGAGGAGGCCACAGAGGCAGAGUCUUCUCUCAUCCAAUCUGCUGCACCCUCAGAUGGCCAACAGCUUGUCCCCACCUCUCCCCAAACUGAUGGCCCACUCAGAGCAUGGUCCUUGUGUCCACAGCAGCAUCCCCUGUGUCCUAGCUAGAAAUGCAGGUUCGUGGGCCAGCCCUGACCUGCCAAAGUGGAGGCUCUGGGGCCAGGGUCCCGGAAAACAUUAACAAGGCCCCCAGAUGCUUCUUCUGUGAACUGCUACUUGGUCCAUGGGGGAAAUAGCACAUAUGCAGGAAGUGCUGCCUGCUCUUGGCCCCCUCCCCGACCAGUGCUGAUGGCCCUGCCUGGCCAGCACCCUCUUGCCUUCAUUCUCCCCCUCCCUCUCCUGUCUUGCCGAGCUCGUCCUCAGGUGUCUAGUGGGCAUCCGACCUAACAGCCUGAGUAGAACCUUCCGCCCACGUAGGUCUUCCCCAUCUCAGUCAAUGACGCUGCCCCAGCCCAGGCCUCAGACCAAAGCCCUGAAGGCAUCCCUGGGGCCCCUCCCCUCACUGUCCACACCCAUAUCAGCAGCCAGCCCUCAUGGCCCCUCCAGAAAACCCUGGGGCUGACCCCAUUUGCCAUCCUCGCUGCCACCCCCGGGGCCUAGCUCCAGUGUGGGCUGUCACUGUCCCCACCCUGUGGAGCCCCCAUGCUGGGACACCGCAGGGACAGGAGAGGGCUGGUCCACAGGACAGAAGAGAGACUUCAGUUUCCAGCAACUUAUCAGAUAAGACCUGCAAACCCUCCACUACAGACUGUAGAAAUGCAGGAAAUGAAGCAGACGCACCUAGCCGUGCCCAUAAAAAAGCAAGGAGACCCACAGGAGCCCAAGACGAAGGAAGUAGACGCGGAAGACACCGUGGGGGCUCACACCGGAGUUGCUCUUGGAAACCACCGGGUUUAGGUUUGGGGGCCAGGUGGCAGAUAGGACUUUGGGCAUCGGGAAGAUGGUGAAAUGCAGUGGAGAUGACUCCUGCGUGAAGCUGGGAUCCUCGAGGGUCAUGAUACUUAACAGUAAAAAGAUGGACUAGAAAAAACAUUUGCCCUCCACCCCUGAGAAUAAGCACUGUGUCCUCUCUCUGCCUGAGAUCCACAGGAGAAAAAGUCACCACUCAUUUAGACCCCACGCUUGUAAUAUCAAUCUGGUUUGCAGACAACCAGGCCAAGAUGUUUAUGACAGAAAACCUCCCUGGAGGGACCUAACUUCAUGCCUUGUUACCUAAGAUCCUCGCACACAAUAGACCCUCAACAUGAGGGCACAUCCUGAAAAUUACAAAACACGUGCAUGAAAGCAAACUUGAAACAGCAGGAUCAGAUCCUCACGAACUUCAAAGAUUAUCGGCAUGUAAACAAAUACACUAUGCAGUCAAUCUGUUGCAAGUGCCUAAAGGCACAGAGACUCUGAAUAGAAAAGAGCAAAAUGCUGUUAAGACAGAGCUGUUACAACAUCCAACAAGGCAAAUAAUUUGCAUGCGGGUUAUAACGUCUACAAAUCAGAAAAAGAGAACCUAACAAAAUGGGCUGUGUGUGAACAGACAGUAUGAAGAAGAUGAAAUACAAAUGGCGACCGUUCGGCCAGGCGUGGUGGCUCACGCCCGUGAGCCCAAUACUUUGGGAAGCCGAGGCAGACCGAUCACUGGAGGUCAGGAGUUCGAGACCAGCAUGGCCAGCAUGGUGAAGCCCCAUCUAUACUAAAAAUACAAGAAUUAGCCGGGUGUGGUGGUGCGUGCCUGUAAUCCCAGCUACUCAGUAUGCUGAGGCAGGAGAAUGGCUUGAACCCAGGAGGUGGAGGUUGCAGUGAGCCAAGAUAGUGUUACUGCACUCCAGCCUGGGCAACAGAGCGAGACUCCGUCUCAAAACACAACAAAAACCGGCCUAGCGCAGUGGCUUAUGCCUGUAAUCCCAGCACUUUGGGAGGCUGAGACGGGUGGAUCACCUGAGGUCAGGAGUCCGAGACCAACCUGGCCAACAUGGCGAGACCCCAUCUCUACUAAAAAUACCAAAAUUAGCCAGGCAUGGUGGCGGGCGCCUGUAAUCCCAGCUACUUGGGAGGCUGAGGCAUCAGAAUCAUUUGAACCCCAGGAGGCAGAGGUUGCAGUGAGCCGAGAUCAUACCACCUGCACUCCAGCCUGGGCAACAGAGCAAGACUUCAUCUCAAAAGAAAAAAAAAAGGCAAACGUUCAACCAUGUAGCUAUUCAGGAAAUAUGUACACAUAAACCAAGACCACAGUUAGAUGCUAUUUGCAUCAUGUCGGCCCCCCCCAAAAAAAUUUUUUUUUUUGAGACAGGGUCUUGCUAUGUUACCCAGGCUGGAGUGCAGUGGCGUGAUCACGGCUCACUGCAGCCUCGAGCUGCCAGGCUCAGCCAAUCCUGCCUCAGCCUCUUGAGGAGCUGGGACUACAAGCACAUGCCACCAUGCUGGGCCAAUUUUUCAUAUUUUUUAUAGAGAUGGGGUCUCGUCAUUUUGUCCACACUGGUCUCCAACUCCUGGGCUUGAGCCAUCAUCCUGCCUUGGCCUCCCAAAGUGCUGGGAUUACAGGCGUGAGCCACCUCGCCACGCCUCCUGAACAUCUAGAACGUGCUAGCUAUGUACUGACUGUGGGAAAGUUGAGAACAUCCUCCCUGAAGUCAUCUUUAUGCCAGAAUUCUCUUGCAGAACUCUAGUUGAGAAAAGCCCUGAGAAGUCCAUGCACCAAUAUAUAGAGAAAUAUCAGGUGUACAGUUACACUUACAGCAGCAUAGUUCAUGAUAGCAGGAAAUUGGAAAGCAACCAAAAGUCCUUCAAUAGGAAAAGGGACCACUGUAGUCCAUUCAUGCAAGAGAUUACAGCAGUGAAAAUGAAUUCAACUAGAGCAGUGAUAUGGCUCAGAAUACAACUUAAACAACAUUGAGCGGGAAAAAUGUUUACAAAAGAAAAUGCAGUAAUCUAGUAUAAAAUACGGAAAUAAUAUUUUGCGUGCUUAGGGAUCUAUAUAUAUCCAGCAAAAGUCUAACGAGAUGCUUGAGAAUUUGAAAAAAUUCACAUCCCUGGUUAUCUCUGAAAGGCAAAAACAGGAAGGGGGUAUGACUGGGGCCUCUGCUGUGUUGGCAAUUUCCUUAAGCUUGGUAUUGCUUAGUGGCUUGUUCUGUAUUCUUUCUUUAUGCUUUUUUUUUUUUUUUUUGACAGGGUGUCACUCUGUUGCCCAGGCCAAAGUGCAGUGGCAUGGUCACGGCUCACUGCAGCUUCAAACUCCUGGGCUCAAGUGAUCCUCCCACCUUGGCCUCCCAAAGUGCUGGGAUUACAGGCAUGAGCCACAGUGCCCAGCCCUUUUUGUAGUUCUUAAUAUACUUUUUGUAGUUUUUUUGUUUUUUGUUUUUGUUUUUGUUUUUUUUGAGACAGAGUUUUGCUCUUGUUGCCCAGGCUGGAGUGCAAUGGUGUGAUCUCGGCUCACUGCAACCUCCGCCUUCUGGGUUCAAGCAAUUCUCCUGCCUCAUCCUCCUGAGUAGCUGAGAUUACAGGCAUGCGCCACCAUGCCUGGCUAAUUUUGUAUUUUUGGUAGAGACGGGAUUUCUCCAUGUUGGUCAGGCUGGUCUCGAACUCCCGGCUUCAGGUGAUCCGCCCCCCUCACCUUCCCAAAGUGCUGGGAUUACAGGCAUGAGCCACCGCGCCCGGCCAGUUCUCUUUUUUUUUUUUUUUUUUUUUUUUUUUUUUUUUUUUUUUUAAGACUGCAAAGCUGGGCAUGGUAGUAUGCACCUGUAGUCCCAACUACUUGGGAGGCUGAGGCUAGAGGAUUACUUGAGCCCAGGAGUUUAAGGACAGCCUGGGCAACAUAGUGAGACCCUGUCUCUAAAACAAACCAACAAAACACCCCCCAAAAAUGACAAUGCAGAUUUGGAAGAAAAAAAUAGAUUAAAAAUGUAGUCAUAGGAAUUAACAACUUGGGGCCGGGCAUGGUGGCUCACGCCUAUAAUCCCAGCACUUUGGGAGGCUGAGGCGGCCAGAUCAUUUUAGGUCAGGAGUUUGAGACCAGCCUGGCCAACAUGGUAAAACCUGAUUGCUACUAAAAAUACAAAAGAAUUAGCUGGGCGUAGUGGCUCAUACCUGUAAUCCCAGCUACUCAGGUGGCUGGGGCAGGAGAUUCGCUUGAACCCGGGAGAUGGCGCUCGCAGUGAGUCAAGAUGGCACCGUUGUACUCUUGCCUGAGCGACACAGUGAGACACUGUCUCAAAAAAAAAAAUUAACAACUUGGUUGGAGGGUGUUAAAAUACAAGUGAGACAUAGAUGAAGAGAAUUAGUGCACUAGAAGAGAGCUGUCUGAGGCAGUUACCCGGGACAUAGCACAGCUAAUGAGACAUAUAUAUAUUUACAGUCAACCCUCCACAUCCAUGGGUUCUGCAUCCAUGGAUUCAACCAAGAGUGAGUUGAAAAUAUUUGAAAAACAAUUGUGUCUGUGCUGGACAUGUACAGGUUUUCUUUUUUAUUGUCAUUAUUCCUUAAAUAAUACAGUAUAAUGAUUAUGUAGCAUCUACAUUGUAUUAGGUAAUCUAGAGAUGAUUUAAAGAUGAUGUGCAUAGGAUAUAUGCAAAUAUUGUGCCAUUUUAUAUAAAAGACUUGAGCAUCCUCAGAUUUUGGUAUCCAAGGGGAGUCCUGGAAGCAAUCCCUUGAGGAUAUGGAGGGACGACUCUGUGUGUGUGUGUGUGUGUGUGUGUGUGUGUAUGUGUGUGUGUGUGUGUGUGUGUGUGUGAUGUGCGUGUGUGGUUAGCACAAGACAAUAAGAAGGCCCAACAUGCCAGCAAGUAUCUAACACAAACCAAAAAAUGAGAACUGGGGAGCAGCCACAUGCAAAGAGAUCGUGGCCAGAAUUUUCCAAAAUUAAUGAAAAUCUUGAAGUGUUUUUUGUUUUUCAUUUUGACGGAGUUUCGCGUUUGUUGCCCAGGCUGGAGUGCAAUGGCGAAAUCUCGGCUCAUUACAACCUCUGCCUCCCAGGUUCAAGCAAUUCUCAUAUCUCAGCCUCCCAAGCAGCUGGGAUUACAGGUGCACACCACCACGCCCGGCUAAUUUUUGUAUUUUUUGUAGAGAUGGGGUUUCACUAUGUUGGUCAAGAUGGUCUCGAACUCCUGACCUCAGGUGAUCUGCCUGCUUCGGCCUCCCAAAGUGCUGGGAUUACAGGCAUGAGCCACUGCGCCCAGCCUGAAAAUCUUGAAAUUUUAAGAUCCAGGAAACCGUUGAGUCCAAAGCAUGAUACACAAACCUAAAUUCGUAACUAAAAUAAUCAUAGUCGAACCACAGAACAUAUCAGACUCAGGGAAGAUCCUAACAGCAACACUAAGAGAUUAAAAUGUCUCUCCAAAGAGCAAUUGGACAGAGAACUGGUUUCACAACUGGAACAACAAAAGUCCGAAGAUAGAGCAUGGCUUCAAAUUACUGAGAGAAGUGCAGUCUAGAAUUCUGAGCCCACCUCAUCUGUAAAAGGUAGGACAAGCCGGGCAUGGUGGCUCCCGCCUGUAAUCCCAGCACUCUGGGAGGCCGAGGCGGGCAGAGGUCAGGAGUUUGAGACCAGCCGGACCAACAAGGAGAAACCCCAUCUCUACUAGAAAUACAAAAUUAGCCAGGUGUGGUGGCGGGCACCUGUGUUCCCAGCUACUUGGGAGACUGAGGCAGACAGAAUUGCUUGAACCAGGGAGACAGAGGUUGCAGUGAGCCGAGAUCGCGCCACUGUACUCCAGCUUGGGCAAAGUGAGAUUCUGUCUCAAAAAAAAAAAAAGACAAGAUAAAAACAAUUUAUCAAUAACAGAUUCCCCGAAAAAAGGAACUUGUGUACAUAAGGAAAGGAAGAAAGAUGUGAGAAGGAAUGCCGGAAAACCUUAGAAACCAUUGGAUCUGUCUAAACUGUCAUUGACUGUGUAAAGCAAUAAUAACAGUGACUAACGUAUAGAGUAGCGACAAAAGGCGCAACUGAAGUACUAGACAACAUCCUGGUGUUCAUGCCUUUCAAGGUCACUAUGCUAUUUGGGAGGAGAUUCGGCUAAAGUCCACGAGGGCCACGUAUUUAUAUAUAAUUUCUAGACCAGUGGUUGGAAAAGGGUUGAAAGAAAACUUUUAACAGAUUAAUAGGAAGAAGGAAAAGAGAAGGAGGCGUAGAAAAAUCAGGAGGCACUGGGCGCGGUGGCUCACGCCUGUAAUCCCAGCACUUUGGGAGGCUGAGGCAGGCGGAUCACCUGAGGUUGGGAGUUCGAGAUCAGCCUGACUAACAUGAGAAACCCCGUCUCUACUAAAAAUAUAAAAUUAGCCGGGUGUGGUGGUGCAUGCCUAUAAUCCCAGCUACUCGGGAGGGUGAGGCAGGAGAAUCGCUUGAACCUGGGAGGCAGAGGUUGUGGUGAGCUGAGAUCGCGCCAUUGCACUCCAGCCUGGGCAAUGAGCGAAACUCCAUCUCAAAAAAAAAAAGAAAGAAAAAGAAAAAGAACAAUCAGGAGGCCAGGUUCAGUGGCUCAUGCCUGUAAUCCCAGUGCUUUGGGAGGCUGAGGCUGAGACAGGUGAAUUGCUUGAGCCUAGGAGUUUGAGACCAGCCUGGGCAACAUGGAGAAACUCUGUCUCUACAAAAAUUAGCCAGGCAUGGUGGCGCACACCUGUAGUCCAAACUACUCAGGAGGCUGAGUUGGGAGGAUCACCUGAGUUCAGGAAGCUGAGGCUGCAGUGAGCUGUGAUUGCACCACUGCACUCCAGGUUGGGUGACAGAGUGACACCCUGCCUCAAAAAAAAAAAAUAAAAUAAAGGAAAAAUCAGGAUAAAUGCAGGGAUGUUCUAAACUUUUUAAAAUAAUAAAUAAUAGUACUUAAAACUGCACUGGGACUUUUGGGACACCCCUAGCAUCUCUGGCUGCAGAAAGCAUAAAAUAAGAUUGUAGAAAUAAAUCCAGAUAUUAGGAACCACAACAGGUGUAAAUGAAGCAAAGCUGCUAGUUGAAGAUGUUGUCGGAUUGAACUGAAAUACAAAAUCCUGUGAUAUCCUGUUUAUACGCGAUACAUCUAAAAUGUAAGUACACAACACAAUUGAAAGUAAAAAAACAUUAAAAGAUGUGACACUUAAAAUAUAAGCACACAACACAGUUAAAAGUAAAAAGACAUUAAAAGAUGCCAAAAGAAAUCUCAUAUGGUUAUAUUAAUUCCAGACAGAAUAGAUGUAUUUAUUUAUUUAUUCAUUCAUUUAAUUUUUUGAGAUGGAGUCUCGCUCUGUCGCCCAGGCUGGAGUGCAGUGGCGCGAUCUUUGCUUACUGCAACCUCCGCCUCCCGGGUUCAAGUGAUUCUCCUGCCUCAGUCUCCUCAGUAGCUGGGAUUACAGGCAUGCACCACCAUGCUUGGCUAAAUUUUUUUAUUUUUGUAUUUUUUUUAUUUUUAGUAGAGACAGGGUUUUGCCAUGUUGGCCAGGCUGGUCUUGAACCCUGACCUCAGGUGAUCCACCCCCACUGGCCUCCCAAAGUGCUAGUGGCAGGUGUGAGCCACCACACACGGCCAGAAUAGACUUUAAAGCAAGAAAGCAAAAGAAAAAAUGUAUUAGAUCCCCGAGAAGUUUCCACACAACUCCAAGAAUUAUUAUUAGAGUUCCCACUCUCUGAGGAAUUUUCAAGAGAAAUUAGUUAGAAUUCAACAAGAAAUAAAUUACUUUAAAAUAUUUCCAAAUAUGAGAGGUUUUUUUUGUUUUUGUUUUUGUUUUUGUUUUUGUUUUUGUUUUGAGAAAGGGUCUCUGUUGCCCAGGCUGGAGUGCAGUCAGUGGCACGAUGUCAGCUCACUGCAACCUUGGCCUCCUAGGCUGAAAUAGUCCUCCCAUCUCAGUCUCACAAGUAGCUGGGAUUACAGGUGAGCACCACCAAGCUCAGCUAUUUUUUUUUUUUUUUUGUAUUUUUAGUAGAGAUGGAGUUUUGCCAUGUUGCCCAGGCUGGUCUUGCACUUGGGCUCAAGUGAUCCACCUGCCUCAGCCUCCACAGUGCUGGAAUUACAGGUGUGAGUCACCAUGCCCAGCCAAUAUGAGAGAUUUUAAAGCACAUUUUUCAAUCACCAUGUGUCAAAGAAGAAAAUAUAAUGGAAGUUAGAAAAUAUUAGAGAAUGGCCAGGUGCAGUGGCUCAUGUCUAUAAUCCCAGCACUUUAGGAGGCUGAAGCAGGUGAAUCACUUGAGCUCAGGAGUUCGAGACCAGCCUGGCCAACAUGGCGAAAAUCCAUCUCUACUAAAAAUACAAAAAUUAACCAGGUGUAGUGGCACACGCCUGUAAAUCCCAGCUACUCAGGAGGCUGAGGCCCAAGAAUGGCUUGAACCCUGGAGGCAGAGGUUGCAGUGAGCUGAGAUUGUGCCACUGCACUCCAGCCUGGGCAACGAAACGAGAGUCUGUCUCCAAAUAAAUAAUUAGAGAAUAUUUUUCAAUCUGGAUGCAGGUGACAUGGGUGUGCUCUCGAGAAUCCAUCAAGCAUUGAUGAUUUGCACACUCUUUUGUGUAUAUGUUACACUUCAGCAAAAACAUUCACAAAGGGGAAAAAGGCAAAAGAUACUUAAAGCAGCCAGAGGUAAAGACACAUCACCUUCAGACAUGACAACCAGACAGACAGACAGCUGGCUUUUCAAAGGAACCCAGAAAACAGUUGGGUGACAUUUUCAACAUGCUAAAAGAAAACCACUAACCCAAAUCAGAGACCCAGCAAAAGUAUUUCAAGAAUGAGGUUACAGUAAAAACAUUUUGCAGACAAAUAACGAAAGAGUUUGCCAGCAGCAGGCUAACACUAAAGAAAAUUGUAAACAGUGUACUCACAUCAGGCACAAGGAAAGUGAUCUCAGACGGAAGGGCAUGAUGCAAGAAGAAAUAAAAGCAAAGAAGUAGAAAAUACAUGAGAAAAUCUAGACAAAGAUUGCAUAAACAGUUUCUGGAGUUUUUUUAAGUGAUAGAAUUAUACAACAGGAAAAAAAGUCUGCAGGGAGUAAACUGAGUUAAAAUGUUCCAAGUUAAUGACUGUCUGGGAGGAGAAUAAAUAACAUGGAUACACUUUGGGAGGCCGAGGCGGGCGGAUCACGAGGUCAGGAGAUCGAGACCAUCCUGGCUAACACGGUGAAACCCCGUCUCUACUAAAAAUACAAAAAAUUAGCCGGGCGCGGUGGCGGGCGCCUGUAGUCCCAGCUACUCCGGAGGCUGAGGCAGGAGAAUGGCGUGAACCCGGGAAGCGGAGCUUGCAGUGAGCCGAGAUUGCGCCACUGCAGUCCGCAGUCCGGCCUGGGCGACAGAGCGAGACUCCGUCUCAAAAUAAAUAAAUAAAUAAAUAAAUAACAUGGAUAAAAUUUGUUGUUUGUUGUUGUUGUUGUUGUUGUUGUUGUUGUUGAGACGGAGUUUCGCUCUUGUUGCCCAGGCUGGAGUGCAAUGGCGCGGUCUUUGCUCACUGCAACCUCUGCAUCCCGGGUUCAAGCUAUUCUCCUGCCUCAGCCUCCUGAGUAGCUGGGAUUACACGAUGCGCCACCAGGCCUGCCUAACUUUGUAUUUUUGGUAGAGGCGGGGUUUCUCCAUGUUGGUCAGGCUGGUCUCAAACUCCCGACCUCAGGUGAUCCGCCCGCCUCGGCCUCCCAAAGUGCUGGGAUUACAGGCAUGAGCCACUGCGCCCAGCCAAAUCUGCAUUUUGAUAAGUAUGCAUUUUACUAUCUAAGGGAGCUAAAACAUUUUUAUUAUUUUAGCACUGUAACUUUGCUUUUCUUCUUUGUUUUGUUUUUUUGAGACAGAGUCUCACUCUGUCGCCCAGGCUGGAGUGCAGUGGCGUGAUCUCAGCUCACUGCAACCUCCACCUCCUGGGUUCAAGCAAUUCUCCUGCCUCAGCCUCCUGAGUAGCCAGGAUUACAGGUGCACGCCACCACACCCAGCUAAUUUAUGUAAUUUUAUAGAGUUGUGGUUUCACCAUAUUGGCCAAGCUGGUCUAGAACUCCUGGCCUCAAGUGAUCCACCUGCCUCGGCCUCCCAAAGUGCGGGGAGACCAGAAUUCCACCCAGAAUGACCUCUCUGUUCCUAGGAGUGUGACAGCAUUUGGGGGGGAAAAUAGCGUAGAGUUGGAAUUUUUAAAAUUCAGUUUGACAAAAUGACUUUUAGCUGGAGCAUUAAGUCCCUUUACAUUUAAUGUAAUAACUGAUAUUACAUUUAAGUAUAAAUUUAAAUCUACCGUCUUACUUUGUUUUCUAUUUUUGUCCUUUCUAUGUUCUCUUUUAUGUCCUCUCUGGAUUUAUUACAGAUUGUUUGUGGCUUUUAAAAAAAGUCAUUGCUUGAAUGAUGAGAGCUUAUAUUUAAAAAGGCAGGGGGCUAAAAUAAAUAAAUAAUUUAAAAAAUAAAAA